CCCCUUGCACAAAACCGAACAUCCCACCCCACCACCACCUCCAAGCUAAAAUACCUGGGCCGCCCCUCCCCACGAAGGGACGCGCUCCAGGCGAAUGGGGAGGGCCCGGAAGUCGGGCCUGGGACAGAGGAGCCGGCCCACCGCCUCCCGGUCGGAAGCGGCAGUGCAGCCCGGAGUCAGAAAGGCGAGGGGCGCCGGGAACUGGCGUGUGGGACUCCAGACAGGAGAGGCUGCGCCUUCCCCGCACCGGGACCUUCGCGACACACCAGAUCCUCGCCCCUGGCUCGCGCGAACGCACAGGAUGACCACCACCCUCGUGUCUGCCACCAUCUUCGACUUGAGCGAAGUUUUAUGCAAGGGUAACAAGAUGCUCAACUAUAGUGCUCCCAGUGCAGGGGGUUGCCUGCUGGACAGAAAGGCAGUGGGCACCCCUGCUGGUGGGGGCUUCCCUCGGAGGCACUCAGUCACCCUGCCCAGCUCCAAGUUCCACCAGAACCAGCUCCUCAGCAGCCUCAAGGGUGAGCCAGCCCCCGCUCUGAGCUCGCGAGACAGCCGCUUCCGAGACCGCUCCUUCUCGGAAGGGGGCGAGCGGCUGCUGCCCACCCAGAAGCAGCCCGGGGGCGGCCAGGUCAACUCCAGCCGCUACAAGACGGAGCUGUGCCGCCCCUUUGAGGAAAACGGUGCCUGUAAGUACGGGGACAAGUGCCAGUUCGCACACGGCAUCCACGAGCUCCGCAGCCUGACCCGCCACCCCAAGUACAAGACGGAGCUGUGCCGCACCUUCCACACCAUCGGCUUUUGCCCCUACGGGCCCCGCUGCCACUUCAUCCACAACGCUGAAGAGCGCCGUGCCCUGGCCGGGGCCCGGGACCUCUCCGCUGACCGUCCCCGCCUCCAGCAUAGCUUUAGCUUUGCUGGGUUUCCCAGUGCCGCUGCCACCGCCGCUGCCACCGGGCUGCUGGACAGCCCCACGUCCAUCACCCCACCCCCUAUUCUGAGCGCCGAUGACCUCCUGGGCUCACCUACCCUGCCCGAUGGCACCAAUAACCCUUUUGCCUUCUCCAGCCAGGAGCUGGCAAGCCUCUUUGCCCCUAGCAUGGGGCUGCCCGGGGGUGGCUCCCCGACCACCUUCCUCUUCCGGCCCAUGUCCGAGUCCCCUCACAUGUUUGACUCUCCCCCCAGCCCUCAGGAUUCUCUCUCGGACCAGGAGGGCUACCUGAGCAGCUCCAGCAGCAGCCACAGUGGCUCAGACUCCCCGACCUUGGACAACUCAAGACGCCUGCCCAUCUUCAGCAGACUUUCCAUCUCAGAUGACUAAGCCAGGGUAGGGAGGGACCUCCUGCCUACUCCAGCCCCUACCCUGCACCCACAUCCCAUACCCUCUUCUCCCUACCCAUCCCAUUCCCCACAGGCCCUACAUUAACAAGGUUAAGCUCAACCCCUUUCCCCCAGCACCUCAGAAUGUGCCCUCCCUCUCCCCCUCAUAACCCCACCUAACAUAAGGACAAGUCAAUUUGUCAGUAGCUUCUUCUGGCUUGAAACCCCCUCCCUGGAUUUUAUAGCCCACUUACCAUGCAUAACAGACAAGUCCCAUAUUUUGUCAGUAGAUGCCUUUUUUUUUCCGGCUUAAGCCUUAAGUGCCAAAUCACAAGAGAAAAAGCAGUAACAGUUUACAGAAGCAACUUAGUGCCUUGUAAUCUAACUUUGUCACUGUGACUACAUUACCUCUUCAGCGCCAGAGGGCACCCGUGGGCCUCCCGGAGCCUCUGCCCAUGGCGGGGUGGAGACCCGGAACCAGCAGCCCCCUCCACUGGCGACACAACUGCACCUUCCCUCAUUUCAGUCUCCCGCACACUUAUUCCUCCUCCCCUCUUCCCGGUGGCACCUCUCCACCUGUACCCGCCCCCCCACCCCCCCCACCCCUGCCCCUUGGAAGAGUUGUUGCCAGACCAGGGUUUUGGGGGAAACCUGUCUUGACAUUCAAAACCUUUUUCUUCCCGAUCUGAACCCCUGUUGACUAAUCUUGCCUGGGUUUGUGUAGGUCUGCAGGAAGGAAGGCUGAAAAAGCGGACGAAGAUUUUGACUUAAGUGGGACUUUGUGAUUUAAUUUUUUCUUUUUUUUAAGUGGGGAGGAAGGGGAAGCUAGAUGGACUAGGAGAGACUUGAUUUUGGUGCUAAAGUUCCCCAGUUCAUAUGUGACAUCUUUUUAAAAAAAAUAACAACAAAAAAAAAAUGAGAGAAAAGCUAAAAAAAAAAAAGUAAGGGGUGAGCAGUUAAUGGUAUUCAUUCCACAUACAAUAUCUGUGUAAAACGAUUUCCUGUAGAAGUAGCUUUAAUGGUUUUUGCUCUAGAAUACCGUAGGUCUAUCCUUAGAGCACUCACGCCAUGCUUUCUUCCCUGGGUUUUAAACUUCAUAUAACUUUCAGAAAUUGGAGAGCAAAAAUUUUGCUUGUCACUGCACAUCAAUAUAAAAAAGCUUAUUUAACUUAUCAAAACGUAUUUAUUGCCAAACUAUGCUUUUUUUUGUUAAUUUUGUUCAUAUUUAUCGGGAUGACAAAUCCAUAGAAUAUAUUCUUUUAUGUUAAAUUAUGAUCUUCAUAUUAAUCUUAAAAUUUUGUGACGUGUCUUUUUCCUUUUUUUCCACAGUUUUAAUAUAUUAUUCUUCAACGACAUUUUUUGUAACUUUACACUUUUUUGGUUAUUUUAUUUUAAAAAAAUGAAAAAUUAAUUUAAAAAAAUGCAAAAAACUGUUGGAUUAUUUAUUUUAGAAAUUCCCCCCUUUGUGUUGGACUGCAAAUUGAGUUUCUUUCUCUUUAGGCCUUUCACAACUAGGACUGAGAAUGUAUGUAAAAGUUCUGUGACAGUACAGAAGGAAAACAACUUUUUAUGUAUAGCUUCUAAAAGGGGAAAAAAAAAAAAAGAGAAACCCUUUGACUUCCACGUGCCCAUCUCAAGACAUUCCACUCACAGAUUUGAGGUUCUGGAUUCCAGGUCUGGAGUUUUCCAAUGUUAAUGUAAACAGAACUGGCACACACACAUUAAGAUGAAUGUAAUUAUUAUUCCUCUUGCUGGUCACUACCGUCGCUUUCUAUUUCUCUUUCUUUGUGUGAAUUUAUUUAAAAGAAAAAAAAACUUUUUGUAACGACUAUUUGCAGUUUAAAAAUCAAUAAACCCCGUUUUUUCAAGAAACAUUGAU